AUUCUGAUUAUAUCACGGAGACUUGCUUUGAGAAAUCUGCCCCUUUUCACUGUGAGAUGGCGUCAUUAACACAUCUAGUUCUCUCCUAAGCAGCCAGCAAACAUUUAUUAUACACUAGAUAUUAUAUUGGCAUUUGAGAUGAUACAAAGGAAUAAAAUGGGGCAAUUAGCUCUAGUAAUUUGGAGGUCUCAACUUACGGAUAUUCCAAGUUCCUUUGAAACGUGUGCAGAAAAAUGUUUAUGCAAAAUUUGCCUACAUUGCAAGGGGUCCAUAGGACCCUCCCCCCAAGUCCUUGACCUCCAGGUUAAGAACUCCUAGCCUAGAAGAGGCCAAUCCCAGCACAAGUGCCAGUGUUAGAAUUGCAUAGCACUAGCUACUGUCUUAUUUAUGGGUCUACUGGUUAAAGGCUGCUUGUGUUUCGACAUCCUUCAUCUUUUAUUUAAAUGGAGCAGCAUCUUACCCUUGAAGACCUUUGGUACAAGAGAGGAAUAUAUGUUUUAAUAAGCAUUUAAUUAACCAGAUCAGACAAAUUAAGAGAAAAAUAUGGUAAAAUGAAAACACUAUUUUCCAAAAAUAUUAACAAUUAAAAUGAAGAUGCCUAAUGUUUAUAACAGAACAUUAAUUUUUUUCUGGUUCCUUUAUUUUUAAUAAAGAAAGAAAAGGAAAUAGAAUUACAAAAAAAACACCUAGAUACUACUAGCUGCCUGUCCACUUUUAUUCAAUCUAUAGUGAGUGACCUAUAGUAAAAGUGACCUAUCAGCCAAGGGUAGGGGAUGUGGACAAAAACAAAUAGAUUUAUCUUAUGAAUGAUUGCUUCCCAAUCCUUCCCCUUUUGCUACAGUGUUUUUGGAGAUUUGUAACUCUGAAAUGGUUGGCAAUAAUUUCUUCAUUUCAAAAUAUUUUUGAAAGCUCAAUAUUACUUUAACAUUAUUGAUAACAAGCCUUGAUUUUACUAAUUCAAAAAUACUUGUAGGAUGCCUGGCAUUUGCAGAACACUGUAAGGUAUUCAGCAAAGAACAGGUGCCAUUGAGGUUGCUGAAGCCUGUUUGUCUGCUUUAUGACAGCCACACCAAAAUUGAAUAAACAUUCUGAAAAAUAACCUCUCUAAAACUGGUUUUGAAUUUAGUAACCAAUAAAAGUCAUAUGCCCCACCUUAAAAAUGAUCCCAUUCUCUUUCAUUCUUUGCCUGGUAGUCAUAAUCUAGCAAUACCAUAUUAGAAUAGUGUGGUAGUAAUCAUAAUAGCUAACAUUCACUUAGCUCUUCCUAUGUGUUAUUCUAAAUAUUUUAUACUUUUUAAUCAUCCCAGCAUCUGUGUGAAUGAAGUUAUCUUAUUCCUGUUCUCCAGCUGGAGAAACUGAGGGUCAGAGUGAUUGAGUAACUUGGCCAGGGUCACAAAAUUAGUAAGAACAGAGCUGGGAUUCAAACCCAGACAGGACCAGAGCCCAAGCUUGUAACCACUUCACCGUACGACCUGUCAGCAGGAUUCUCACCCAGCUCCCCACAUGGCCCUCAUGACACAUUGAGCCUCAGUUUCCUUAUCUUUAAAACAGGGAUAAUUUAAGUUAGGCAUCUAGCCAUUGCCUACCACACUGGUACUGAAAACUGCUGUUUCUGCCGGGGGCAGUGGUGCACGCCUAUAUUCCCACCUACUUGGGAAGCUGAAGUGAGGAGGAUCACUUGACUCCAGGAGUUCCAGACCAGCCUGGACAACAUAGGAAAACUCCAUCUCCAAAAAAAAAAAAAAAAAACAAAAGUUUCUAUUGCCUGCAAAGAGAUCACAUUAUAAGAUUCUACCAUUUCUAAGGAAGAUAUCUGUAUUUGCUUCCUAGGGCUCUUGUAACAAAUCACCACAGAUUUAGCGGCUUAAAACAACAGAAGUUUGUUCUCUGAUACUCCCAAAGGCUAGAAGUCUGCAAUCAAAGUGUUGGCAGCGCUGUACUUCCUCCAAGGGCUCUAGGGAGAAUUCUUCCUCACCUCUUCCAGCUCUGGUGGCUUCAGGCAUUUUUUUUUGGCUUGUGGCUUCCUAACUCUGAUCUCGCCUGUCUUCACAGGGCCUUCUCUGUGUCUCUCUUUUAAAAACAGUUGUCCUUAGAUUUAAGGCUAAUCUGAGUAAUACAGGAUGCUCUUUUUUCAAGAUCCUUAACUUAAUUGAACUACAAAGACUCUUCUUCCAAAAAGGUCAUAUUCACUGCUUCCAAGACAUGAACAUAGGUUUUGGGCGGCUAAUAUCCGACUUACUACAAAAUCCCAAUAUAAGUAUUUUUAUGUUUUGGAAGAUUCCCUCUGGCCUUCGCCCUGACAACAAGCCAGCUUUAUUCAGAGGGAGUAAAUCAUUUUAUCUCACCACUCCUUUUCUUUGCACUGGAAGCAUGUAGGUAGCCAUAUGGCUGGGAGCAGGUGAAGGAGGAUGAACCCAACAGUAAUAUAUCCACACUAUUCUCAGGAGAAUCAGAAAUCCACUUGGCUAAAUUGUCAAUGAGAGUUUUUUCUUUUAGUAUAUCAUUGCAGUAAUUCACUUCUAAGUAUAAGAUUAUAAAAUCUAAGCGAUUUAUGUGCCUAAAGCAACAUGUUUUCACUGAAUACUCAUGAAUUUGACUAUAAACUUCUACUUUCCCUUCUCACCUCCCCUCUGUCUCUGAAACCAUCUAACCUGGAAUACAGCAGUAUAACCAACCAAGCAGGGAAAUGUCCCUUGAUUCAGGGGUUGGCAGAGAGAGCACCUUAUCAACGCUAUGCGUGUCUCUAUGGCCUGAUCCGCCUAGUUCUCCACUCUUUUCUUUUCCUUUUUUAUUUUUAUUUUUUUUUCUUUUUGAGACAGAGUCUUACUCUUUUGCCCAGGCUGAAGUGCAGUGGCAUGACCACAGCUCAGUGCAGCCUCAACAUCCUGGGCUCAAGCGAUCCUCCCACCUCAGCCCCUCAAAGUGCGAGGAUUACCACGCCCAGCCUCCACUCUUUUCUGUAAAAGCGCUAAUAAGUGAGAUGCAGAAGCAGGUCAACUGAGGGCAAUGAAAGGGCAGCAGGCUAGAUUACUACUGUCACAAAAUCACAUCUAUGAAAGUUCAAUGUUGUCAGUCACCAAAAUAAGAAAAACACUGACCUCAUCACCACAGCUUUCCAGAUAAUGUAAUAAGAAAUAAAGAAUAAGCAGAAGUGGGAGAGACAGAUAAAUAUGUUUUUUUAAAAAGUUGUAUAAACAUAUCUAUUCAAUAUUACCCAAAAAAGUGAAAAGAAAACAGACAAUUAGUAUUAGAAAACACUAUUGGAAAGGUCUUGGCUGACCAGCUCCUUAUACAACCAGAUUUGCUUUGGCAGAACUCUGAGAACAACGUACUCCUGACAGAUCAAUAUUGCAGUAACUCACCAUUUUCACCCUCAAAUUAUUCACUGGAUAAAAAUCUUCAGUUGCUGAAGAUUCAUAAAAUGUAAUAACAAUAGGUAGGGAAGAGAAAAAGGCUUAACUUUUCAUGGUCAGGCUUCUAGCUCUUAAGAAAAACAAAGGCCUUAGAAAAAACAUCAAGCAAGUCUUUCCUAAGGCAGUUAAGCAUAUCAUAGAAUUCACAGUUCCCACAAGUACUGUAGAAGAUUAAGCUAUUAGAAUUUCACUGAUGCCAGGAAUAAACCUAAAUAUGUCAGCUGUCAUCUCAAGAAGGUUCUUGGGGGUUUGGCUCUUCUGAGUUUUCCCCUUCUAUUUUGACAACCAAGAAGGGAACCCCAAUUGGGACCUCACAAUUAUUAUUUGAAGACCUUUGGGGUUAUUUGUUUACUCAGCUUUGUAUGGUACAUCGAUGUGAUUUUGCUAGACUAGUAAUGCCCCAUUCCAACUUGAGACUCUUAUUGACUUUUAAUAACUUUUUAAAAAUAUUAUUCAGACUGUUUUAAAGUUUAUUUUAAAAUUUCAGUCCUUCAUAAUUUUUAGGGUUAUUCAUUGAUUUCUUAAAAUGUUUAAUUGUGGUAAACUACACAUAUAAUUUAACAUCUUAGUCAUUUUUAAGAGUACAGUUAAGUGGUGUUAAGUAUAUUUACAUUGUUCUUCAACCAAUCUCUAGAACUUUCUCAUCUUGCAAAACUGAAACUCUAUACCCAUUAAACAAUAACUCUGUAUUUCUGCGUCUCCCCAGUCCCUGACAACCAUCAUUUUUCUGUUUCUAGGGUUUGACUACUCUAGAUACCUCAUGUAAGUGAAAUCAUACAGUUUUUGUGACUGGCUUAUUUCACUUCAACAACAAAGGCUCAUCCAUGUUGUAGCAUGUGCCAGAAUUUCCUUCUGUUCUAAAGCUGAAUAAUAUUCCAUUGUAUGUAUACACCACAUCUUAUUUUUCCAUCCAUUUGUCCAUGGACAUUUGGAUUGCUUCCAUCUUUUGACUAUUGUGAAUAAUGCUUCUGUGAAUGUGGAUACACCUUUAAUGACUUAGAAAACAACUUUUGGUGGCUUUAAUGCCAUUGUUAAUGUUGCAGUUUGUUCACUUUUUGCUUCUAAAAACAACCUGGCAGCCCUUGGCAACAAUAUAUUCAAAAGGAAAAAGCCACUCAGAAGUUAUAUAUUUUCCCUUUUCCUUCUUUAUAUAACAACAAAGUUUCUUUUCUUUUUAAAUAAAAUAGUUAUAAAGAAGCUCAUACUAAGAAAGGACAUUGUAGCUAAACCUUGACCUAGAAGCCCUACUCUCCCUUCCAGUAUUGCCAGAAAUAAGCAGGGAUACUUACCCUGUUUCUGUUAGGAAGUGAAAGGACAGCAGAAGCAAGACAAGAUAGACCAUUCCCUUGUUACAAAUUUCUCUUCCUACUCCUAAUAUCUCCUCAGCAUCAAUGUAUGUGGCACUCUUUAUUUUCUAAAUGUUUCUUCUUUUUGAUAGCCACACAAUACUGAGAUUAAUCUAAUCUGAAUUUAGUAUUUUCUAUAUUAUCAUGAGAAUUUUUGUUAAAGUCGAAUUCCAAAUUUUCUUUCCCAGCUGGAAGUUUUUCAUUCAUAAAUUCCUCUGUAGUCUAUCAGAAGAUGACCAAAAAAUAGGACUGCCUUGAAAUUGCAGUUACUCAACACAUGCCAUGUUGCACAAUGACUCCAAUUGAUAGUUGGACUAGAAAUACAUGUUUUUUAAAUUGUUUUGCUUUUGUUAGUGUUAAUACAAAUGGAAGGUAAUAAAAUUGGUUCAGGCCAGGUGUGGUGGCUCACGCCUGUAAUCCCAUCACUAUGGGAGGUCAAGGUGGAAGGAUCACUUGAAGCCAGGAGUCUGAGACCAACUUGGGCAACAAAGUACAACCUGGCCUCUACAAAACUGUUUUUUAAAAAUUAGCUGGGCAUGGUGGCAUGUGCCAAUAGUCCCAGCUACUUGGGAGGCUGAGGAAGGAGAAUAUCUUGAGCCCCGGAGUUCAAGGUUGCAAUGACUGUGGUCAUGCCACUGCACUCCAGCCUAAGUGACAGAGCGAGACCUUGUCUCAAUAAAUAAAUGCAUAAAUAAAAUAAGGUGAGUUCAGGUAGCCAUAAAACAUUCUGUUAUUGUAUAUAACACAAAACACUGUAUCAACAACAACCUGACUGAACUGUUAGUGAGACUUUUUCCUUCUAGUAUAUUAUUUCAGUAAACUUCCAAGUAUAAGAUUAUAAAAUUUAAUUAGAGUAACUUUGCUGCCUAAAGCGAUAAUGUGCUUUGACUUACAAUUGUUUGUUUCUUAUCUCUAGAGGGUCUAUAAAAUUAUCCAACUAAUGAAUGUGUAGAGAAAGUUCCUUAAUUGCCCUAUGGUUGUUCGAUUUUCUUCCCUACCUUUGAUUCAUCAUAAACUUUUAAGUUGUUUUUUUCAGCUUCCCCUAAAAACUUGGACUCCAAAUCUUCACCUCUGGUCUGACUUCUGGUAUUCACUCUGCUGUCAACAUGAGGAAUUGGUUGCCAAAGGAAGGCUGGGGAGUAUUCUAAGAUGAAAAGAAAAUUCUCCUCCAAAAGUUUAAACAAGGAUGGAAUUUUCUGUAGGGCACAGAAAACAUUGGGGUCACCCACAGAGAAUGUAGAGCAAGGUAUCUGGAAACUGAUCAGCCAAUAAACUGAGGUUAUGUCUAAUUCUUACACAGAAGCAAUAUAAGGUUUUGCCCCAUUAAUCAGAUAAACUUAAACCACAUUCAUGUGUCCGAUACAAUAAGAAAUUGCAUGUCUUUGUAUCUCUGUGAAUCUAAUUGUGCUCACAUGAAGAUGCAGCUUGUGAUUAGGCCCCCGAGACAAGAACAAUCACAUUGGUUGUGCAGUGCACAGCCCACACAACAGUAUGUGGUGGCCCUGCCCAAGAAAUAUUUCGCCAUUUGUUUACAGGUUCCAAUACCUUUCAAGUAGUGAAGCCAUGUAGCAAUCAUGGCUACAAACGUGUGUAUUUAUUUAUUUAUUUUAAGGUACUAGAUGAUUCAAUUAGCAAACAUAAAUAAGGGGUAGUUUUUUCCCCAUCAAAUAUACAAAUCACUCCAUUGUUGAAGUAACUGUUAUAUUCCACAAAGACUCUUUGAGUCUAUAAUUUAGUAAAAUCUUGCAAGUGGCUUAAAGUUUUACAAAUCUACAAGUAAUGACAAGACACUACAGUUGCUGUGAAUAUUACUAUUAUGUCUAAAGAGCUAAAACCCAUUCCAACUCUCCUUACUACAUCACUCAAACAGGCUCAGAGACAAUUAUCAAUUAUCUCAGUUUUACACAUGGAGAAACUGUGACACAAGAAGAUUUUGGAAUUUACCCAAAGACACAAAUAAAAUAAAUAAAUAGAAAGAGAGGAAAAGAGCUGCAAUAGAAUUCAAGUCUUCAAGUGUCCAGGUGUUCCCAUCCUGGAAUUUUUCCCAUUAGAACCACUUUUCUACCUACCAAUCUUAAAUUAUUACUCACCUAGAGUAAGCACUUCUAAGAGCUAUUUCAAUAGGAUUUAAAACUAAUUCAUAAGUCUUUCUUAUUCCCCUGCAGAGUCCAUGAACUUUUAACAUUAUAAGAAAGUAAAAAAGCAUUUGUUAUAUAUAUUUUUAAAAAUUUAGCACCAGCUCCCUUCCAUGCUUCAAAAAAACAGAUUGUACUGAAUUUUCACAAAACAAUCUGUCUAAAACUCAUUGCCUGAAAGCAGACAAUGAGAAUUCAGAAGCACCUUUUAUGAUCCCCACAUUGUGCUGUGGAAAUAUUAAGUACAUUCGAGUGUGCUUCCUGCCUUCAACCACCUUACAACUGAAUCGGUCAGUCAGCCAACAGGCCAGCUCACCAACCAGGCACUGGGGAUAAAAAGAUGAAUGCUGCACAUUCCCAGUACCCAAAGCCCUCAUAGUCUUGUGGGGAAACAGACUGUGCAUAACUAAAAAUGUUGCUACAAUGGUAACACAUAAAAGAGAGUAAUAAUAUUUUCCUUUGCAGGGGAGGGGUCUUCUGAGAAUGUUUCAUAGAAGAAAGAAUAUAGAAGAUAUGCCUUAAAAUAGCUUCUUUAAGCAAUAGCUUAAAAUAGGAGUUUAUCUGGCAGAGAAGGGGCACAAGAAAAUUUCAAGAAAAGAAAAGAGCAUGAAUGAAAACAUAGAAGCUUUAGAAUGAAUGGCAUUUAGCAGGAGAGUUGAGAGAUUUAACUGGAGAGGUGAAGAAAUGAAACUGUGAAGGGCUUUAAACGAAGGUUUUAUUUCAUAGGAAAUGGAGAGCCAUUGAAGGCUUUCAAGAAGAGAAAUGAAUCUGUUAAGUUUGGACAGUUAAUUCUAGCAGCAGUUUAGAAGACUGUAAGGUAAAAAAGAGACAAGUAGGUAGCUAUUUCAUUAGUGCAAGCAACAGAUGGAGAGUCCACAGCACCAUCCAACAAAAUAUUCUGCAAUGUUGAAAAUAUUCUAUAUCUUUUCUCUCCAGUAUGGUAACCACUAGCCACAUGUGGCUAUUAAACACUAGACAUUUAAAUUGUCAUGUGUGACUAGUGGCUGCCAUAUUGGACAGUACGGAGACAUCUUAGAGAAGCUAACACUUAAGCCUUAAAGUUGGAUUUUUCCAACUGCAGGUUGCAAUUAGUAGGUUAAGAAAUCAAUGUAGUAAACACAAUCAUGAUGUUUUUAAUGAAAGAAGAGAAUAACAAAAUAAGGUAGAAUUAACUAGAAUAGAUAAGAAUAAAUAUAAUGGAACAGAAUAGAAUAAAAAAUAUCAGCAUGCUCUGCAAAGUAUUCUUUUGAGAGAUGUUUGUUUCAGUUAUAUGACUCUCUCUCUCUUUCUCUCUCUCUCUCUGUGUGUGUAUGUGUGAGUGUAUACACCAUGGAUCACAAUGUAAGAUGUAUUUUUCCUCUUUAUUGUGUUUAAGAAAUUUUAAAAGCCAGUCUCUUAUGCAAGGAUAUUACUCAUCUAUGUACAUAGUUAUUGGGAAAAAUUUUCCAGAUAGGAAGUAAAGCUUCAGCAAAGUUCACUGGAGUUUAGAAUAGGGAUAACUCUGGACCUUUGAAGGCUUUCCUAAUUAAUCUUUUCUCUUUUGGAUCGGCUUCAUUGUUUAGGACAGUUGUAGAUUUACAGAAAAAUCAAGAAGACAAUACAGGGAGUUCCCAUAUACCCUGAAUCCAGUGUCCCCUUUAAAAUCUUACAUUAGUAUAACAUAUUCAUUACAAUUAAUGAACCAAUAUUGAUAUACUAGUAUUAACUAAAGUUCUUACUUUACUCAUAUGUCCUUAGUUAUUACUUAAUGUCCCUUUUCUGUUCCAGGAUUCCAUCUGGGAUACCACAUUACAAUUAGUCAUAAUGCCUCCCUUAGCCUCCUUUGGCUAUAACAAUUUUUCACAGUUUGCUUGUUUUUGAUGACCUUGGGGGUUUUGGGGAGUACUGGUCAGGUAUCUUGUAGAAUGCCCCUCUAAUGGAAUUUGUCUGAUACCUUUCUCAUGAUUAGGCUGGAUCUAUGGGUUAUUGGGAAGAAGACCACAGAGGUAAAGUGUCUUUUUUGACAUCAUAUCAUGAAGAUUAUUCAUAUCAUGAUUGUUAUCAACAUGACUAAUAAUGAUCGAUGUUGGCCUUGACCACCUGGCUGAAGCAGGGCUUAUCAGUUUUCUCCACUGUAAAGUUACUCAUUUUUAUCCCCCCUUCCAUACUGUGUUCUUUGGAAGGAAAUCGCUGUAUUUCUAAUUUUUUAAAUAAAUGAAUUACUCAGUUAAAGGAGGGCUUGUACUUGAGUAAGUCAUAUUAAGCUGUUUCCAAAGAAAGCUACUGUGAGUACAGAAAGAGUCUCUUUUUAGAUACAGCAUCUCUCUCUGCAACUGGCAGGACACUUUUAUCACUUCUCAGAUUUUCAGGUUCCAAAUAUGAAGCACAAAAAAAAAAUGAAGCUGAGUGAUUGAUGUAGAGUUCCAAAGUGAGUUGAGAAGGAGUUAACCCAAAAAUCAACUUUAGGCCCUUCUAACUGUUCAGUCCCUGAUUCUGAUGUUCUAGAAGUAAAUUUAAACCAAAAUGUACUAAGUCUUUUUUUUCCCCAGGAGAAUAGCUACCUUUAGAAUAGGAAAUUCCUUAAUGAGAAAAUCCAGUAACUUGGGGUAGUUCUUUUUUGGCAGGGGGAGGGCUACUGAUCACGUCUUCUGCAAUAUUUCCAAGGUAAAUACCACUGUACCAAAUCACCUGCUACGCCUCUUUCAUUGCAGUUACCUAACUUCCUUCCAGUCCUGUUCCCCAAAACAGAAAACAACAACAAAGAGCUCCCUGAGCAAGCCCAGCCAAUACUUUUCUUGCAAGCUCCCCUCAACUGUGUUCACAUUCCAUGACUCAUACAGCAGUGUUCGUGUUACCACAUGUGGUUUUUUUUAAUUGUUACAUUUAUUCACUUUCUUCUCCAUCCAAGCCAGAACAAAGUCCUGCCCCUGUGUAAUGAGUCAUAAGUCUCAAAUCUUCUCCCUCUCUAUCUGAGAGAGGAGAUGUAACUUCAUCUCCUUCUCCACCGCACACAAAUCUAAUGAGAGGGAAAUCACCACCCGUUGAUAAAAGAGUAGUAACAAUCAGAAAUAAGAAAUAAUCAUUUACUCUGCAUUCCCAGUUAUGAAAUAACCUUUUAGUGGACUUCCAACACAGAAACAUUCAGGCUACAGCCGGUAUUAUCACUGUCUCAGCAUGUCAGAGUCAAACUGUAUCCAGGCCACUGUACCCCUGCCUGAAGCCACAUCACAGUCUGCUUAGGAGUGCCACCUUUGAAUACACAAUCUCAUGAAAGAUCUAAGAACAUUUUUAAAGUCAUCAAGUUUAGAGGAAACUUUUCUUUUUAAAAAAGAAUAAACUACUCUCUCCUUCUUUUCCAUAUAUCGAAAGUCAUCUUUUCAAAAGCACCUAACUAAAAACAGGAGAUGCAUGGUGUGCCUGAAUAAAGACAAACUUACUGCAGCUUGAAGGAGCCAACCAUGGAUUUGAGGCGUGUGAAGGAAUAUUUCUCCUGGCUCUACUAUCAAUACCAAAUCAUUAGCUGCUGUGCUGUUUUAGAGCCCUGGGAGCGAUCUAUGUUUAACACCAUCUUACUAACCAUUAUUGCUAUGGUGGUAUACACUGCCUAUGUCUUUAUUCCAAUCCACAUUCGCCUGGCUUGGGAAUUUUUCUCAAAAAUAUGUGGAUAUCACAGUACAAUUUCUAAUUGAUCCUGUUCACAUUCAGUGAAAUGGCAUUGCAUAUUUAUAUGUUGCUUACAGCUUAUUGAUUUAGGUAACUAUUGUGUCUUCCUUCACUAUCUGACCUGAAAAGCACUCUCUUCUCUAUGCACUCUUAUAUUCUGCCUUUCUGCCUGGAGUUUGAAAUACAUGUCUCUUUAGUUUCUUUUGCACAUGCUACAUUGUGCUUUAGACCGGAGAUAAUACAGUGACUUUACCUCACAAAUCAUAUUCUGUCAACACAAAUCUAUGAAUUUAGUUUAUUUAAAAUCAGAACAAUUUCCUACAAAAUUUUUCUGGAAAAUAGACUCCUAACAGACCUACCAGAAUCAUGCUUAAAGUGCUCCCUUGACACUUAUUCUAUACUAAAGGAUAAAUUUUAAAAAAUCUUUAUAGGCUACUGUCAGAAGUAUCCUAUCCUUGUUUACGAUGUAUAAAAAGAUGUGAAUAAAUUAUAUGGACCCCCUAAGUCUUAUUUUCUAGUAAACUGAUGAUACUGGAAAUUCUUUUACUUCAAAUGCAAAAGAAUAAGCUGGAGGCAAUUAUUUCCUUUCAUACAGAGUUCAUGAAUUGUUUUAAAUGCUUCUUAAAGUCUGGCUUUAUAACCGUUUAAAAUCAACAAUGUUGAUUUUAGAUAACCAAGUAAGUAUUAUAAUACAAAAUAAUUUUAAGUGUAAGAAACUAAAGUAUAAUCAAAGUAAAUUCAGUUAUUGUAUUUGUGGUGUUGCCUUGCCUUGCAUGAUGCUGGGGGAAAAAGAGAAAAGAAAUGGUUUUCUUUUUGUACUUUCAUUCAGUGUAGAGGGAAAAAAGCAUGUAUUGGGCCACCGGAAGACAAGCUAAUAAAUAGGCUGGAAGUAAUAUUCUACCAGCAGGAACUCAACAGCUCCAGUUAAAUGCUUUGAUAUAGUGGCUCCUUUGCAGAGCCAAAACAAGAUUUAUUAAAUUUCCUUCAAACUGUUUAUCUUUAAAACAAAUAUAAGGUUUUAAUUAUACUGCUGAAGCAAAUGUGAAUGCCAAAGACUACGUUUUGCAGUUUUGCUUUCCUCCCAAUAAAUAUUAAUGUAUGUAAUUCUAGAGGGUAAAAAUGUAAAUAGGUUUGGACAAUAUUUGCACCCUUGUUUGUGUUAUGAAAAAAAUUUUUCCAAGGUGAGCUAGAGAGAAAGAUGUUUGGCAUGCCAAAUUAACUUGCAUGUUUGUUAAAAAAACAAACACAUGUUUUGAAGAGAAACCAGAUCUGAACAUGUAUUUGUUGAGUUUUGCAAAAUAAAAUUAAUUUUGUAAGUAAA